AGUGCGAGAUCCGCUGCUGCUGAGGAGAGGAGCGUCAACAGCAGCACCAUGGUAGCUGUGAGUAUACUACAUAAUUUAUAGAGUUUUUUUCAGUCUCAGUUAACUUAAAUUUAAUUUAUAGUUGGAUGAAAUAUGAGCCAAGGAAACCUUAGGUUUAAUGCAUAUUUCUAACUCCACUCAUAGCAGACUUUCAAAUAUUUGACUUAAAAAUGUUAGAUUCUGAUUAGUCUCCUAAUUAUUAUGUUUAUAGUUAGCUUUUCAUUUUAAUGGGCUUCGUUUUUAAAAUUUGGCUUAAGAAUUAGUUUUAUGAAAUGAACAAAAGAGCCAAAGAUUAUGGAUGGAAUAUUUAGCUACAUGACUAGUAAACAUUGUAGACUUCUGUUCUUUGUUAAAUCCAAAUGUAUUGAAUUGAUGUUUUGAUCCCAUGAUUGCUUUUUAAAUGAGAAUUUAAAUGUGGCAGAAACUUUUAAGAGAAUGUGUGCCUCUUUUUGCUAUUUUUUAAUGUUGAGAUAAGACUGCCUCCAAAGUAAAAUUAACCAAUGAGACUCUGCUUAUUCAAAUAGUCUUAACUACGGACAGCAUUUCUCACCCAUGGCAACAGAAGAACCUUGAAGGCUAUGUGGGAUUUGCCAAUCUCCCAAAUCAAGUAUACAGAAAAUCGGUGAAGAGAGGUUUUGAAUUCACGCUUAUGGUAGUGGGUGAAUCUGGAUUGGGAAAGUCGACAUUAAUCAACUCAUUAUUCCUCACAGAUUUGUAUUCUCCAGAGUAUCCAGGUCCUUCUCAUAGAAUUAAAAAGACUGUACAGGUGGAACAAUCCAAAGUUUUAAUCAAAGAAGGUGGUGUUCAGUUGCUGCUCACAAUAGUUGAUACCCCAGGAUUUGGAGAUGCAGUGGAUAAUAGUAAUUGCUGGCAGCCUGUUAUCGACUACAUUGAUAGUAAAUUUGAGGACUACCUAAAUGCAGAAUCACGAGUGAACAGACGUCAGAUGCCUGAUAACAGGGUGCAGUGUUGUUUAUACUUCAUUGCUCCUUCAGGACAUGGACUUAAACCAUUGGAUAUUGAGUUUAUGAAGCGUUUGCAUGAAAAAGUGAAUAUCAUCCCACUUAUUGCCAAAGCAGACACACUCACACCAGAGGAAUGCCAACAGUUUAAAAAACAGAUAAUGAAAGAAAUCCAAGAACAUAAAAUUAAAAUAUACGAAUUUCCAGAAACAGAUGAUGAAGAAGAAAAUAAACUUGUUAAAAAGAUAAAGGACCGUUUACCUCUUGCUGUGGUAGGUAGUAAUACUAUCAUUGAAGUUAAUGGCAAAAGGGUCAGAGGAAGGCAGUAUCCUUGGGGUGUUGCUGAAGUUGAAAAUGGUGAACAUUGUGAUUUUACAAUCCUAAGAAAUAUGUUGAUAAGAACACACAUGCAGGACUUGAAAGAUGUUACUAAUAAUGUCCACUAUGAGAACUACAGAAGCAGAAAACUUGCAGCUGUGACUUAUAAUGGAGUUGAUAACAACAAGAAUAAAGGGCAGCUGACUAAGAGCCCUCUGGCACAAAUGGAAGAAGAAAGAAGGGAGCAUGUAGCUAAAAUGAAGAAGAUGGAGAUGGAGAUGGAGCAGGUGUUUGAGAUGAAGGUCAAAGAAAAAGUUCAAAAACUGAAGGACUCUGAAGCUGAGCUCCAGCGGCGCCAUGAGCAAAUGAAAAAGAAUUUGGAAGCACAGCACAAAGAAUUGGAGGAAAAACGUCGUCAGUUCGAGGAUGAGAAAGCAAACUGGGAAGCUCAACAACGUAUUUUAGAACAACAGAACUCUUCAAGAACCUUGGAAAAGAACAAGAAGAAAGGGAAGAUCUUUUAAACUCUCUAUUGACCACCAGUUAACGUAUUAGUUGCCAAUAUGCCAGCUUGGACAUCAGUGUUUGUUGGAUCCGUUUGACCAAUUUGCACCAGUUUUAUCCAUAAUGAUGGAUUUAACAGCAUGACAAAAAUUAUUUUUUUUUUUGUUCUUGAUGGAGAUUAAGAUGCCUUGAAUUGUCUAGGGUGUUCUGUACUUAGAAAGUAAGAGCUCUAAGUACCUUUCCUACAUUUUCUUUUUUUAUUAAACAGAUAUCUUCAGUUUAAUGCAAGAGAACAUUUUACUGUUGUACAAUCAUGUUCUGGUGGUUUGAUUGUUUACAGGAUAUUCCAAAAUAAAAGGACUCUGGAAGAUUUUCAUUGAGGAUAAAUUGCCAUAAUAUGAUGCAAACUGUGCUUCUCUAUGAUAAUUACAAUACAAAGGUUCCAUUCAGUGCAGCAUAUACAAUAAUGUAAUUUAGUCUAACACAGUUGACCCUAUUUUUUGACACUUCCAUUGUUUAAAAAUACACAUGGAAAAAAAAAAAACCCUAUAUGCUUACUGUGCACCUAGAGCUUUUUUAUAACAACGUCUUUUUGUUUGUUUGUUUUGGAUUCUUUAAAUAUAUAUUAUUCUCAUUUAGUGCCCUCUUUAGCCAGAAUCUCAUUACUGCUUCAUUUUUGUAAUAACAUUUAAUUUAGAUAUUUUCCAUAUAUUGGCACUGCUAAAAUAGAAUAUAGCAUCUUUCAUAUGGUAGGAACCAACAAGGAAACUUUCCUUUAACUCCCUUUUUACACUUUAUGGUAAGUAGCAGGGGGGGAAAUGCAUUUAUAGAUCAUUUCUAGGCAAAAUUGUGAAGCUAAUGACCAACCUGUUUCUACCUAUAUGCAGUCUCUUUAUUUUACUAGAAAUGGGAAUCAUGGCCUCUUGAAGAGAAAAAAGUCACCAUUCUGCAUUUAGCUGUAUUCAUAUAUUGCAUUUCUGUAUUUUUUGUUUGUAUUGUAAAAAAUUCACAUAAUAAACGAUGUUGUGAUGUAAUAUUGUGUGAGGUCUUAAAUAUCCUACAGUCGAUGUACAAGAGUAGAGUAUGUUUGGGAAGAAACUUUUCAGCUUAAGUUUGCCUCCUCUACAAUGACAUCUUUUAUAUGCUUGUCUCAUUUAGAAUGCAUAUGUGCUGAUUUUCUAAUUUAAGAGAUACCAUAUCUCUCUAUUCAUUUCUAUCUCUCAUUUGUAUGCUUAUUUUUCUGAGAACAUUUUUUUUUUCCCCCAGACAGGGUCUUGCUUCAUUGCCCAGGCUGGAGUGCGGUGGCACAAACACGACUUGACUGCAGCCUCAACCCUCUGGGCUCAAGCAGUCCUCCUGCCUCAGCCCCCUGAGUAUCUGGGAUUGCAGGCGUGCACCACCACGCCUGGCUAAUUUUUGUAUUUUUUGCAGCCUCCCAAAGUUCUGGGAUUACAGGCAUGAGCCGUCAUGCCUGGCCUCUGAGAACAGUUUCUGACUCAUUCAGAUUAGGUAUACUCUCAAGUCCCUGGAAACUGAAAUUUUUUUUAACUGUAAAGAGGGUAGUGUCAUUUCUUUUCUUAAGGUCAAGUGACAUAGAUUUUAAUGUAAUGCAUAAUUUAGGUAAGAAAUUAAUUAAUGUAGCCUAGUUUAUUAUCUUGAAAUGUUUUACCCUAUUUACUUUUUAAAAUUAAUGACCUAAGCGGAGGGAAUAAUUAUAAGUCAAUAGCAGAGAGAUUGUUGUUUGGGUGUUUAUUUUUUUCAGUUUUUGUUUUGAGAGAUUGGGUUAACACCUCUAGCCAAAAUUGUUUGGUUUUAGGGAGGCUAACAAUAACCUACUGAAUUUGGAAAAUGCAAAGGUAAAAAAUGUAUAUAGACUGCCUGCUGAACUGGUUAAGUACUACUGCUUCUGGGAAAUACUAUUUCAAAAUUCUAUGUAUUAUAAUAAUAAAUUUGUAAGACAUUCAUUAUUCUACCAUCCUAAUGAAAACUUUCAGAAGUCUUUCUUUAUCCAUGGCAUGCCCAGGGUUUUACCUGAAUCUGAUACAGGAUCUAUAUAACUUUACUAGGACUUUUGAUUGUUGACUCCAGGCUUAGGUAUAUCAGAAGGUUCUUUUUGCCAUUUGGCCUGUGGAUGUCUGAGAAGAUCAUUCACAAUACAUGUAAAAUUCAGGUAGGCCUAAGGAAAGGCCAGCCUGUAGAAAGCAAAAUGGCAGUGUCUGUUCUCCACUGUUGGAGGCAUUAUGUAAUUUAAGUAUCCUGUUAGCCACUGUCUUUCUGCUAAUUAAGUGGGGCUGAACAAGUAAGCACUAAUAAUACCAGUGAACCACUUGGGCACCUUGUGGGUAGAGUUUUGCUGCCACCUAGUGGAAUGGGAUAUCAUUGCUUCCAUAUCAGGUUCACAAGCAAGUUAAGUGGGCACAGUUUAUUUCUGUGUAGCUCAGGCUGUAAUCUUGAAAGCUGAGGAGAUACCCAUGCCUCUCAGACUCAUUAGCUGGGUGUCACAUUACCACCUGCACAUUCUGACCCACCGCAUCUUAAUAUGUUUUGUCCUCUUGGAGAAACUAGGAGUAGAAGUCAGGAUAUGGUAGGUAAGGGGGAAAAAGGAAAGACGGCUUGAUAGCUAUGAAUGCAUGAGGAGCGAAAUGUUGACUCAGUUAUCUAGAUCAUGGUCUCCAAACCUGAUGCUAUUUCCUUACAAAAAUAUUUGUUGAGCAUGUGUCCAUAAUUAUAUGUAUUGAACAAUGAAAAUAUGUGUCAACAAAUGUACUGCUACACUAAUGUGAACAUUAUGGAACAAAAUUUGAAAGAGUGAAAUAAAAGGUUUACACUUUCCCCAA